GCCAGGCUCGCCGCGGGGCGCUGAGCAGGCCGGGACACCGCGGCCGAGGUUAUCGUUAGGCAUCUCCCAGGCGACCGGCUCCGCAGCAAGAUGGCGGACGAGAAGGACAGGGAAGGUGAUUUGUAUGUACAUUAACUUUCGAGAAGGCCGGGCGCGGUGGCUCACGCCUGCAAUCCCAGCACUUUGGGAGGCUGAGGCGGGCGGAUCACGAGGUCAAGAGAUCGAGACCAUCCUGGCCAACAUGGUGAACCCCGUCUCUACUAAAAAUACAAAAAUUAGCUGGGCGUGGUGGCACGCCCUGUAGUCCCAGCUACUCAGGAGGCUGAGACAGGAGAAUUGCUUGAACCGGGGAGGCGGAGGCUGCAGUGAGCCAAGAUCACACCACUGCACUCCAGCCUGGCGACAGAGUAAGACUCCGUCUCAAAAAAAAAAAAAAACAAAAACAAAAAACAAAGUUCGAGAAGCACUCAUGUGCUGUAUCUCAUUUAUUGUUAACAGUUUUAUGGAUUAACUAAUUGCAGUUUGUGAAGGGUAUUAUGAAAUAAAGGCAUUUUGUUAGAGGAUAAACUAAGUAGAGACUCAUUUUGGUGGUAAGAUCUUUUUAUGGAAAUAGUCUAUUACUAUAUUUGAUUGUCAGCUACUGUAUUUUGAAUUUUCAGAAAUUACGUCUAACCAAUUAAUCAGAAUUGAUUAAGUUUUGAGGAUUCACUCAACUAAACUCAUAAAAGACUGAUGUGCAAACCUGAAUGAUUUAUUAAUUUAAAUAAGGGUAUAUACAUUGACUUGAAGGCUGAUUUUGCCAAUAUACUAAUAUAAUAAUUUUGGCAAUAUACUAAUAUAAUAAUAUACUGUUUUAUGGGUACUAAGCUUCGGGUAGUGUGAAUUUGUAUUUCAGAAGUCAUUUGAUGACCGUGGAAUCACACAAAAGAAAGGAUAAUUUUGAAGGAUGUGUUCAGUACCCUCUAAGUUCCAAAAGAUCUGGGACCAUUUCUGAUCUGUUAAUACUGAGUGUUGUGCAGAGUGCUUGGAACGUGGGCCUGGGAUACAACAGUGAUGAGAUAAGGCCUCGGACUUUACUGAUCGAACAUCUAAUGGAAGGUGGAAGAAGAGACCAUCACACAAUGACGGUGUUAUGGGGAACACAGGAGAUAAUAGUAGCAGAAUUUCACAAAAAAAUCAAAGAGGCAUUUGAAGUCUUUGACCAUGAGUCGAAUAAUACAGUGGAUGUGAGAGAGAUUGGAACAAUUAUCAGGUCAUUAGGAUGCUGUCCUACGGAAGGAGAGCUGCAUGAUCUGAUUGCAGAGGUAGAGGAAGAAGAACCCACUGGAUACAUUCGAUUCGAAAAAUUUCUUCCGGUGAUGACAGAAAUACUACUAGAAAGAAAAUACAGACCAAUUCCAGAAGAUGUCCUUCUUCGAGCUUUUGAGGUUUUAGAUUCAGCUAAACGUGGGUUUCUUACUAAGGACGAGCUGAUCAAGUAUAUGACUGAAGAAGGCAUUGCAUUCAGAGCAUUUCCAGAAUAAAAGAUAUGCCAUCUGGAAAACAUGAACUAUCGAUCACUGUAAAUGAAGGCCUCUUCCUAGAUUGAAGAUUUGAAUAAAGAAUAUAAAAAUUCCGCCCCCCCCCCGGCGCCCCGGCUUUUUUUUUUUUGAGACGGAUCCGGUCUUGCUCUGUCACCCAGGCUGGAGUGCAGUGGCGCGAUCUUAGCUCACUGCAACCUCCGCCUCCUGGGUUCAAGUGAUUCUCCUGCCUCAGCCUCCCGAGUAGCUGGGAUUACAGGCACAGGCCACUGCGCCCAGCUAAUUUUUUGUAUUUUUAGUAGAGAUGGGUUUCACCAUGUUGGCCAGGCUGGUCUCGAACUUCUGACCUCAGGUGAUCCACCCAUCUUGGCUUCCCACAGUGCUGGUAAAAAUUCCCUUUUAAAGAGCUUUUCUGUCAGUGAAGUUACAGAUAAUGUAGCCUCAAUUGAAUACUGAGGUCAUUUUUAACACUAAAAAUGUCCUUUUUUAAUGUUAAUUGAACCAUAUAUAUUUGUUUUGAACAUGGCCCAUCAUACAUAUAUGCAUACACACACAUAAAACCUGCACACUUAUAUAUAUAUGCCAACAUAUUUCCUUUAGGAAUUCUCUCUGCUAGGCUGAUGUGUAAAUUUGUUUACACUGAAGGUCAGUAGCCUGAUGGACAGUCUCCUGAAACCAUCCUCAUAUUGGUCCCCUUGCCUUCUCCCAUACAAAGCUAGAGCUCUCUGGUUCACAGACUGGGUCCUGAAUGACUCAGAGUUGCUAAUCACUUGAGGCAGAAUGAAAAGCGCAAGUGAUUUUGAGUAGGGAAGACUAAGACUGCAUCUACACGCACAACUGGUUUGACCAUUCCAGCUUCAUCCACCUUAAGGCGGAAUACAGAGAGUGAGGGUCAGAAUGGCAAGGCCGUCACAGCUGCCACCCAAGAACUCUGACGCCAUUGUUAAAAUUACCUUCGGGAUUAAUUCUGAUGGGGAUGUUACGACUUUCAAAGCAUCAGCUUCUUCAUCCUGAGGAUUAGUCUAAAGAAAGUAAAUCCUAGGUUAUAUAUCAGGCAACAUGAAUUUAGUCAAAAUGGCCCAAACAGUUAGAUUUUCCUACUGUUGUGUGCCUACUAUAUGUUUAAUAUUUAGUAAGUGUAGUAAGGUAUAAUGAUACUUAAAUCUACUUCCUCUCUCAAGGAUAUUACAAUCUUAUUUGGGAAAUAAAACUAACAUAAAAUAAUUCACAAUACAAGACAAUAGAAAGCUAAAUAUCAGAAGAUCAACUAGGGCUGGCCCAGCCUGGAAAACUUGGUUUGGGAAGACUUAAAGAGAAAAUAGGUUUUUUGAGAUGGUAGAAUGUAUAUGGUUAAAUUGUUGAGGGCAAAGGUAAACUCUUGUGCAUUAUAAUUCUGUCACACAUGGUAGAUAUCAACAAAUGUUUGUUGAAUGAAUGAGUGAAUGAGUAGAUGAUGAAGACCAGGUGAAGGGGCUAAUGAGAGGGAGACAUUAUCGAUGUGUAAAACAGUCUGAACAAAAAUGGGGAGGUAGGAAUGAACAUGCUAUUUCAGAGAGAAAAUAAGCCUAGCUGGCCCAGAGGGUAAUGUUGGCAAACAGCAGGAAAUUAACUUCAGUAGACUUACUGGGACUAAAUUGUGGAGUCCCAGGCUCAGGAGUUUGGAAUUCAUCCUGUGGGCGAUGGAGAAGUAUUACAGGCUUUUGAGCAGAUGACUCACAUGGUGUGUGAGUGAUUGUGAGAAGGUUUUUCUGGUGCUGGUCGGUUUGUUAGAUGCAUAAGAAAGAGGUUGGACUAGGGAGGCCACUUAGAAGGUUAUUUCAGCAUUUUGAGGGCACCCAAAUAAGGGCCUGACCUGGCAGUGGGAAUGGCAAUGGGAAGAAGGGAUUGGUACAAUAGGACUGUCUGUGGCAGGAUCCAUGGGUCAUGAUGAGUAACAGAGUGUAGGCGACAAAGCUGAGAGCUGAAUCCAAAGUACCACCAAGGCUUUGCCCUCGAUGGCGAGUAUGAUGGUAAUGAGACUGACUCAAACAGAAAGGUCAGAACAGACCGCAGUGUAUACAGAGACAGUGCGACCACGUGGUUUACUUGGAGGUGCUGUGUGAUAAUUUCGAAAAUGGUAUGUUUACAGAGAGUUCAUGGUACUUAAAGAUCAACUAUUGAGUAUCUCAGCGGACUAAGCAUAGGACAGGUAUGGUCAAAUAAGAAUACAUAUGUUUUCAAUUAUUCACUCAGCAAGUAUUAUUACAAACCUUCCACAUAUAUGAACCAAUAUGUUUGGAAGUAAUAUGUAAGAUGUAAAUCUAUACAAAUCUAAGUUACGAUUUAAUAUAACAGACCCAUCAGCUAAGUGUAAUAGCAGUUGACUAGUUUGGUAAAAUAGGAGCUUAAGAAUUGCUGCUUUGAGAGUCUCAGAAUUCUACAAAUUGUUUUUAAGUACAUUUAUGCUAUAUAACAAUAUGGAUUCAAGCUACUUGCACAUUCAUCCUAAUAUCCACAAAGUAUCAAACACACUAGUUUGAGAAUAUGCAUUCCUACAGCCCUGGAUGUCAUAUGAUAAAAUAAAUCACACUGAAUCAAGUUCCUACAAGAUAGAAGUCCCUAAGUGUCCAGGAAUGUGUAUUGCAUCAGACAGUGUUUAGCAGCCGGGAAGAUCUCAGAACAAUUUUUUAAACAAACACUUGCAUGUUGCUGCUUCUAUGCCAGGUACUGUUCUAAGUCCCAUUCAAAUCAUAACACGUUUCAUUCUCAUGACAACCCUAUGUGACAGGUGGUGUCGUUAUCACCCCCAUUCUAGAGACAGGUAAGCUAAGGUGGGGAGCUGUGAAGUGACUUGCUCAAGAUCUCAGAGCUCGUGAGAGGCAGCCAGCAUGUGGAUCCAAACUUGUGCUUUAACCACUCAGUUAUCUUCCUUCCAUCUUUCAUCAAAUACUGGGGCUUCAAGUUAAUCCUCUGGUAAUUUCAAAAGUUUUAAUCUAAAUAAAUAACCUUGUUCAUGAUGUCUGUAUGUCUUCCUACUGUUUUGCCUGAAAUGACGUGUUCUAGAGGUUGCUUGAUCUAUGACAUCUGCAGGCUAAAAGAAGUCCAGAAUCUACCAGGGUGUACAAUAGCCUUGUCUUUGAACCUCUGGACUGUCGUGAUGUCCUGGCUCUACAGCUCCAGGGAGCGUAACUAGUGGCACUGUGGGAGCUUGUGGGGCUCCAUGGCUAUUAAGCUGGCUAGUGGAAAGAGAAAAAAAUCAGAUGAUCCUAAAUGAUAAAUUUUCCUUUUUGUCUCUCUGAGGUGAGCCUUUUUCUCAAGAGGAAAUGGAAGAAAUGUUGUCUGCUGCAAUUGAUCCAGAAUCAAAUUCAAUUAAUUACAAGGACUAUAUAACAAUGAUGGUGAUAGAUGAAAAUUAAAUGUUCUAAAGAUAAUUUCUGAUUGAAAGAACAAUUUUAGAAAUUGCUUGUUCUUGUUAAUUUCACAUCUUAUCUUAGGAUUCCUAUAUGUGAUAUUUAAUACCUUGUGACAUAACUAUUUUAAGACACUUUGUUUUUAAAGAUGAUCGUAACACUUUAAACCAAAUUUAGUAUGUCUAGCCUUACAGAAUGAUAAAUUACUAUUUAUUUAAAAACUAUUCUUAAAACAUUUUAACAUUAGAAUGGAUUGUUGUUUAUUUUCUACAAUAAAACUCAGGUCACCUUCGAAUUAAUUAAGCUGACAAAAUGAAAAUGACUUAAUUACCCAAGGUUUGGCAUGUAAAGAUCUUAAGAGGGGGCAGAACGAACCACUCGAAAACGAGUAGCAGUGUAAUGAAGGCUUCUUUUUUAAACAAUAACAAAUGCUUCAUCAAUCUGAGUGUGGAAGGUGAUUUAUCAAAAUAAAUAUUACUAAUUUAUUUUUUUAUGAGUGCCAAUUACAAAUAUCAUUUGGGAUAAUAAUAACUUAGUGUAAACAUUUAUAUUUGCUGAUCCAGCAUGUCACCAUUUAUGGAGUAGCUAAAGGAGUUGAGAUCAUUGGAACUAGAGAAAAGAAGGUUGAGUGGAAGUUGAUAGUGUAAGGUAGUGGCAAUUCUCCCUUUGUCUUUAGAAUUCUCACCCACUCCGCAUAUCUGUCAUGGGAGCAUUGUCCUGAAUACUGAGUAAGAAUACUGAGAAAUGUUAUGGUGUGCAAAUGUACAGCUCCUGAAAGAGCAGAAUGAAGCACAAGCAGUCACAAUGGAAAAAUAUAUGGCAUGGCCACUGCCUCCUCCUUGCAAUUCUCUCCGAUCUUGGCAUCUUAUAUGGCAACUAUAUGGCAACUUACAAGCAAAGGGGAAGAUAAAGUAAAGGGAAGUGAACAAUUUUCCAAACUUAGAUAUUCUGUUAUAACAAGACACACACACACACACACACACACACACACACACGGGUCUCUAUUUGAAGAUGGCUUCACCACUAUAUGUGUGUAUCUACAUAGAUGUAAACAUUUAGAGUUGCUGUGAGCCUUCCUCAGGCAUGUAGUCUUGCCCCCAAAAGAGGCGGCUGCUACCCAAGAGACUGUCGCUGUUCAUUCAUUCAUGAAACACUGAAGGAGUACCAUGAGAUGAUGUGCUGGGAACCGGAGUCCCUAACGAAUCCAGGUCACAGUUUAGUGAGGGAAGCCUGCAAGGCAGUCAGCAGCCACAUUUCAGAUAGGGGCAUGUUCAGGGUCCCGUGCAAGUGCCGAAGAGAGGCAGCUACUCAGCCUUGCAGGGAGAGAGCUUUCUGGAAGAUGAAAGGUGCUAGUGAGCGGAGAAGGCUUCCCAGGACAGGAAGCUCCUGACUUUAAAACGAGUAGUUUAGUAAGUGGGUGGCGGGGCACAGGGCAUUUCAGCAGGUGAGCAGCAAGUCCAGAAACCCUAGAGGUGUCAUGAAACAUGGAACCACCUGGGAAUUGAAAGCAGCUCAGUAUAUUUGGAAUGUGGGAGAUUUGGGGGUCAUGAUGAGAGGUGAAAUUGGAGUGGUAAACAGGAGCGGUAUCAUUAAGGAUAUCGGGUUAGGUGCUGAGUUAAGGUUUCAGUGUGAGAGUUUGGACUUUAUUCUGAAGAUCACAGAGAAAGAUCAUUUGUAAGCAGCAUGGAAAAUAGAUUUGAAAGGUCAAGACUAGAAGUGAGACCAGUUUGUAGGCUAUUUGGUUGGUGGGAGGGGAUAGACUGGGAAAAGUCAAGCAUGAAUCCCAGGUUUCUGGCUCGGACGAUGGGUAAAAGUGCCAUUCAUUCAGAUAAGAAGUCCAAGGAGCAAGUGGGGCAUUUGGUAAGCAAAAUGAUGAGGUUGGGUGCAGACACCUUGGGACACCCAAAGGGUGACAUUCAAUAAUCAAUUGGAUAUAGGAGGGAGAUCUGGCUGGAGACCUGGAUUUUGGAACUGUCAGCAUGUAAGUAGUAUUAAUGCCUUGAAAGUAGAAGAGAAGACAGUCUAGAACAAAACCAUGGGGGAUAUCAGCAUUUACGGGAAGGCAGAGGAAGAAGAGCCCACAAAAGAGACUGGGAAGGAGAAGCCUGAGAAGAGGGAAAGCUGGAAAGAAGCAUCUUGGAUGCCAAGAUCGGAGAGAAUUGCAAGGAGGAGGCAGUGGCCAUGCCAGAUGUAGUGGAGAGGAGAGGGAAGUUAAAGACGGAAAAAACGUCCAUUGGUGUUAGCAAUGGAGAGUUCAUUGAGGGCCUCUCCCACAGCAGAUGUGGGGAAGCAACAGGGUAUGGAGUUGAGUGGAUGGAGUAAGGAAUGGAUGUGAGAAGGUUGCAGCCUGGAGGACAAGUUAUUCGGCAGUGAAGAGGAGGAAACGGACAACAGGCUCGGGGAGUGAUUUUUGGAAGAUGGGUGGAUGUAGCAAGUUCAUUUCUAGUCCAAGGGCUGAGAGCCCACAGAGAAGGUGAAGGGAGGGGCCAGCUUCCAGAGCAAUAAAGAGAUUUAGGAACAAUGAACCAACGCUUGUGGUCCCUACCUCAUGGCCUCUGCUGCCUUUUGGAGAGGAAGGUAGUAGGUUAUAGAGUUUCAAGAGAAUGGUGUAAUUUUGGAAUAUCUCUUGUGGGAAAUGGGAGAAAGAGUUGAGAAAGAGCCCAUGUAAGGAUUUUCAAGAAACCCUGGAAGAUUUUGUGCUCAGGAGCAAAAAAGAAAAGAAAAAGGUAGAUUGUUGUACCAGGGUUAAGGUUUUGUCAUGUGCGUGAGGUGGAAGGAAUCAAAGGCCGAGGAAUCUGGGAGAAAGCAGUUCCGAUGGUGUCCGUGGGGCUAACGCAUGAGGGAAAGACCCAGGUAGGAGGAGUGGGUAACAGGUAGGAGGAGUGGGUGACAGAUGGGAGGGGGUGAGAGGGCUCGGGGCCCUAAAAGGGCAAGUGGCUGGUGUUGGUAGCAAGGGGUGGUCUUUCCUGCCUGAGUGAUAAUUCCUGAGUGAUAAUAUGUUUCCCUUGAAAUUUCGCUUCGAUGUGUUCUUAGAGUGUUUCUUUUCUUCUCCUGUGUUAUUAUGUGAAUAAAUAGUAAGAGUGGCUGA